AGUGCUGCUUACCCAUCAUGGAAGCAAUGUGGCUCCUGUGUGUGGCGUUGGCGGUCUUGGCAUGGGGCUUCCUCUGGGUUUGGGACUCCUCAGAACGAAUGAAGAGUCGGGAGCAGGGAGGACGGCUGGGAGCCGAAAGCCGGACCCUGCUGGUCAUAGCGCACCCUGACGAUGAAGCCAUGUUUUUUGCUCCCACAGUGCUAGGCUUGGCCCGCCUAAGGCACUGGGUGUACCUGCUUUGCUUCUCUGCAGGAAAUUACUACAAUCAAGGAGAGACUCGUAAGAAAGAACUUUUGCAGAGCUGUGAUGUUUUGGGGAUUCCACUCUCCAGUGUAAUGAUUAUUGACAACAGGGAUUUCCCAGAUGACCCAGGCAUGCAGUGGGACACAGAGCACGUGGCCAGAGUCCUCCUUCAGCACAUAGAAGUGAAUGGCAUCAAUCUGGUGGUGACUUUCGAUGCAGGGGGAGUAAGUGGCCACAGCAAUCACAUUGCUCUGUAUGCAGCUGUGAGGGCCCUGCACUCAGAAGGGAAGUUACCUAAAGAGAGCUGCCCUCAGCCGAGCAGAGGCAGUGGUUGGGGAGGCCGCCACACUCUUCCUGACUCACCUCAAGGUACCUGGCAGGUUGUAUCUACCAGCAAGUGCCUGCCUGCAGGGCCACCUCUGGAUGAGUGGGGAGGCCAGGUUUGCCCCUCAACCUGUCUAGCUUUUUCACAGGGUGGAUGUUUUACACCUCUGGUAUUCUUCCAGUCUGAACUCAAUCCCAUCCCCCAACCAAUUAGGCAGGUUGUAAAUGACUGCUGGGUGCUUGAUGAACCAAUCUGCCUGAGUUAGGAACUCUUCCUAACCCACAUAAAGUAUUUGACCCUACCUGACCAUUUACUGCAUGACCCCCAUGCUUAGCCUCUCUGGACCAGUUUCUGGUCUGUCAUACCUCACCGGCGCAAUACGAAGAUUCAAUGAAUGAAAACGUAAGUAGUUUGUGCCCUUUCUAUGUGGGAUGACUGAAAGGAGCUUACCAAGCCAUGAUGACUUUGGAACAUGACUAUAGUUUGUUUGAUUCUUAUAUCAAUCCUGUGAGACAGGCAGGUCUCACACUAUCAACACCAAUUUACAGAUUAGAAAACUGAGACUGAGAGUGGUUAAGGGACUUUGCCAAGUCUGUCAAUUCUUGACUGACAGAGCUGGAACCAGGUCUCUAAACUCCCAAUACAGUAAUUCCUGUCUCCUUUACUUCCUUUGGCUUUGAGGUAGCCAGAUCUCAACCUCUAGCAGCCAACCUUUUUCUGGUAGGGCACACCGCAGGGUAGAGGGUAGCCAGCCAGGUCUUCUAUGGCCCUUUUACUCGUUCUAGCUGCAAGAAUCAUGGGCACAGGGCAGCUUUAGUGCCACAGAAACACGUGGCAAUGCUGUGGCCACUGUCCUGCCCUGCCCUGAGCCACAGGGUAGAGGGAGGAUGCUCAGGGGAAAAUCUGGCUGGAGGCCUCAAGGCUUAUCACUUCACCCUGUCUCCUCUCCAUCCAGGGUGCUCUGUGCUCACGCUUCAGUCUGUGAAUGUGCUGCGCAAGUACAUCUCCCUUCUGGAUCUGCCCUUGUCUCUGCUUCAUACGCAGGAUGUCCUCUUCGUGCUCA